GCCUUCCUCCUCGUCCUUUAGCCGGGAGCCUGUCUUUGCUUGCCUUUGCCUUUGAGGCUCUGUGGCUGUGGGGCUGAGUGGCAUCAUGGCGGCUCAGAAAGAUCUCUGGGACGCCAUUGUGAUUGGGGCGGGGAUCCAGGGCUGCUUCACUGCAUACCACCUGGCCAAACACAGGAAGAGGAUCCUCCUGCUGGAGCAGUUCUUUCUACCACACUCCCGAGGAAGCUCCCAUGGACAAAGCCGGAUAAUCCGAAAGGCGUACCUGGAAGACUUUUACACCCGGAUGAUGCAUGAGUGCUAUCAGAUAUGGGCCCAGCUGGAGCACGAGGCUGGAACCCAAUUGCACAGGCAGACUGGAUUACUGCUGCUGGGAAUGAAAGAGAAUCAAGAAUUAAAGACAAUCCAGGCCAAUCUGUCGAGGCAGAGGGUAGAACACCAGUGUCUUUCAUCUGAGGAACUGAAGCAACGUUUCCCAAAUAUUCGGUUGCCCAGGGGAGAAGUGGGGCUCUUGGACAAUUCCGGAGGAGUUAUCUAUGCAUAUAAGGCCCUCAGAGCCCUGCAGGAUGCAAUUCGACAGCUAGGAGGCAUAGUGCGUGACGGAGAGAAGGUGGUGGAGAUAAACCCAGGGCUACUGGUCACGGUGAAAACCACCUCCAGGAGCUACCAAGCUAAGAGCUUGGUCAUCACAGCAGGUCCUUGGACCAACCAGCUCCUCCGUCCCCUGGGCAUUGAGAUGCCUCUCCAGACCCUGCGGAUCAACGUGUGUUACUGGCGAGAGAUGGUUCCUGGGAGCUAUGGUGUGUCCCAGGCCUUUCCGUGCUUCCUGUGGCUGGGCUUGUGUCCCCACCACAUCUACGGACUGCCCACAGGAGAGUACCCAGGGCUGAUGAAGGUCAGCUAUCACCACGGCAACCACGCAGACCCUGAGGAGCGGGACUGCCCCACAGCACGCACAGACAUCGGAGACGUCCAGAUCCUGAGCAGCUUUGUCAGAGAUCACUUACCUGAUCUGAAGCCCGAGCCUGCUGUCAUUGAGAGCUGCAUGUACACGAAUACCCCUGAUGAGCAGUUCAUUCUCGAUCGCCACCCAAAGUAUGACAACAUUGUCAUUGGUGCUGGAUUCUCUGGGCACGGGUUCAAGCUGGCCCCUGUGGUGGGGAAGAUCCUGUAUGAAUUAAGCAUGAAAUUAACACCAUCUUAUGACUUGGCACCUUUUCGAAUCAGCCGUUUCCCAAGCCUGGGCAAAGCCCACCUUUGACCUCUGGCCAGAAGCCUCCCUUCUGUGCACAGGAGCCAGUUUCACAGAUGGAGAAGAUGUCUCAGAUGAAGGGAGUGUCCCUGAGAUAUCAUCCUUUUCUUCUGCCUCGCCUGAAUCCCCCAUAAACACCAGAUGAUUGAGUCUACCUUCUUUCCUUGGCCCGCUCCCUUUUUCUUCUGCCUCACUUGAAUCCCCCGUAAACACCAGACGAUUGAGUCUACCUUCUUUUCUUGGCCACCUCCCCAUUCACAACUACUUUCUCGCUCCCAGAAGGUUGAUCAGAUAUUCUACAAUCACAGAGUAGCAAGGACGUUUGAGAUGGGUAUAUCAGUAAGAAGAGGGCACAAGAACUGGCUCUGGAGACCAAAGCAGUUGUUAAAAAUUCUCUUUGCUGGGGGCCGGGUGUGGUGGCUCACACCUGUAAUCUCGGCACUUUGGGGGGCUGAGACAGGCGGAUCACCUGAGGCCAGGAAUUCAAGACCAGCCUGGCCAACAUGGUGAAACCCUAUCUCCACUAAAAAUACAAAAUUAGCUGGGUGUGGUGGCGCAUGCCUGUAAUCCCAGCUACUUGGGAGACUGAGGCAAGAGAAUCACUUGAACCCGGGAGGUGGAGGUGGCAGUGAGCCGAGAUUGCGCCAUUGCACUCCAGCCUGGGCAAAAAGAGUGAGACUCUGUCUCAAAAAAAAAACAAAACAAAAAAAACCUCUUUGCUGGUAUAUUUGAAGAGCUUGGGAUGGAUUUGACUAAAUCUGCCCCGAGGAGGGUGAACAAGGUGAUCUCAGAGAUCACUACUGCUCUUGGAGUUCCUUCUCCUAAAGCUAAGGCCAGCCUCCAUCACAAAUGCCCAUAAAAUCUGGCUCGUCUUUGAUGAACAAUAAAUAUUUGUUGAACAAAUAAAUAACUGCCCUGCA